AGGGCGUUGGGCGGAAGGGGUUCGCACGCCAAGAACCGCCAUGCCUGGGGAUCACCGCCGCAUCCGCGGCCCUGAAGAAUCGCAGCCGCCGCAGCUGUACGCGGCCGACGAGGAGGAGGCGCCCGGCACCCGCGACCCAACGCGGCUACGGCCCGUGUACGCGCGCGCCGGGCUGCUGAGCCAGGCCAAGGGCUCGGCCUACCUGGAGGCGGGAGGCACCAAGGUGCUGUGUGCCGUGUCGGGCCCGCGACAGGCCGAGGGCGGCGAGCGCGGCGGCGGCCCGGCCGGAGCAGGCGGCGAGGCCCCGGCCGCGCUGCGCGGUCGCCUGCUCUGCGACUUCCGCCGCGCACCCUUCGCGGGCCGCCGGCGCCGCGCUCCCCCGGGCGGCUGCGAGGAGCGUGAGCUGGCGCUGGCGCUGCAGGAGGCGCUGGAGCCGGCUGUGCGCCUGGGCCGCUACCCGCGCGCGCAGCUCGAGGUGUCGGCGCUGCUGCUGGAGGACGGUGGCUCGGCCCUGGCCGCCGCGCUCACCGCCGCCGCGCUCGCCCUGGCCGACGCGGGCGUGGAGAUGUACGACCUGGUGGUGGGCUGCGGCCUCAGCCUCGCGCCGGGGCCCGCGCCCACCUGGCUCCUGGACCCCACGCGGCUCGAGGAAGAGCGCGCCGCCGCCGGCCUCACCGUGGCGCUCAUGCCUGUGCUGAAUCAGGUGGCCGGGCUGCUGGGCAGCGGCGAGGGCGGCCUGACAGAGAGCUGGGCGGAGGCCGUACGCCUGGGCCUCGAGGGCUGCCAGCGCCUCUACCCCGUGCUGCAGCAGAGCCUGGUGCGGGCCGCCCGCCGCAGGGGCGCCGCCGCCCAGCCCUGAACCAGAAGCCUGAGCAACUACGGACGCAAGCCGAGGACCGUGCUGCCGCCGUCCACGAAAAGACCCGCGCCAUCGGCCUCCAGUUUGCGUCGAGAAUUCCUGGAAGGGCCCUGAUAUGACUGUGGUUGGACUGACCUGACUGCCAGAUGGUGGGACUUGGUCUGGAGCAGGGACUACUUGGAAUGAUAAAGGCAAAACUCAACAGCCCCUGGAGCUGCGCUUGUGGUGGAGCUGGACCCUGAAAUUACCUGGACCUUUUUUUUAGAGACAGGGUUUCUUUCUGCAGUCUCAAACUCCUAGCCUUGAUUGAUCCUCCUGCCUUGGCCUCCCAAAGUGCUGGGACUACAGGUGCAUGCAACCACACCUGGCUAAUUUUCUUUUCUUCUUUCUUUCUUUUUUUUUUUUUUUUUUUUUUGAUGGAGUCUUGUUCUGUUGCCCAGGCUGGAGUGCAAUGGUGCAAUCUUGGCUCACUGCAACCUCUGCCUCCUGGGUUCAAUCCAUUCUCCUGCCUCAGCCUCCCAAGUAGCUGGGAUUACAGGCACAUGCCUCCAUACCGGGCUAAUUUUUGUAUUUUUAGUAGAGAUGGGGUUUCGCCAUGUGGGCCAGGCUGUUCUCGAAUGCCUGACCUCAGGUGAUCCACCCGCCUUGGCCUCCCAAAGUGCUGGAAUUACAGGUGUGAGCCACUGUGCCCAGCUGAGUAAAUUUCUUGAUUGCACAGAAUGUACGGUGAUAUUGGCGGACUUAAGGACAUCGAAUUGUUUAUCAGGAAUAAAGUAUUAUGUGUGUUUUCUGCGGCCCUGGAUAAUGCUGUAGCAUUCAGGGUCGAUUGAGUAAAAAAAAUGUAGAGAUGGUUUCCUGUUUGUUUUUGCUUCUAGUUUUCAUUCAUUUGCUAUUUAUUCUCUUCUGGCUUUGCUUGUGUAUGCAUAUAUAUAAAACCAUUAUUAUUAUUAUUAUUAUUUUUAGUUUCUAGUGGAAGGCUUUUAUUUGGUUCUGUGAAUAGUCAUUUUGUUUCCUAAGAACUUCCAGCAAGUUGUAUUCAUUCCAUUCAUCUAGAAUUCCUAGGCUGCCUUUGUCGGGCCUGCAGGUAUUAAUGGAGAAUAGCAGCUUUUUAUUUUUUUAUAUUUAUUUUUUGAGACAGAGUCUCACUCUGUUGCCCAGGCUGGAGUGCAAUGGCGCGAUCUCAGCUCACUGCAACCUCCGCCUCAGAGGUUCAAGUGAUUCUCCUGCCUCAGCCUCUGGAAUAGCUGGGACUACAGGCACCUGCCACCACACCCAGCUAACUUUUUGUAUUUUUAGAGAAGAUGGGGUUUCAUCAUGUUGGCCAAGCUGGUCUCAAACUCCUGAUCUCAGUGAUCCAUCUGCCUCAGCCUCCCAAAGUUAUAAGAUUUUUUUCCUCUGGUUUUUAGUAAAUGUUUUUUUUGAGAUUGCUUAGCACCAGAAUGAUUUGCAAAUUUGAAAAUAGGAACUCCACUAGGAAUGCCGGAUAGAAGAGUGCUUCACAUUUGUAGAGGGAGACAAGAACUAAAUAUCACGACGUCUUUCUGAGCCUUUUGGUUUGCUAACGUGCCCCAAAUUCUUAUUCCAAACGGUAUAAGAUAAUUAUGUGUAAAUGAAUACCAGCUCUACUUAGUUUUAUUUCAUAUUUGUGUAUCUGAAUAUAUUAAAAUAUCUUUUUUUUUUUUUUGAUGCGGAGUCUUGCUCUGUUGUCCAGCCUGGAGUGCAGUGGCAUGAUCUCGGCUCACUGCAACCUCUGCCUCCCAGGUUCAAGCGAUUCUCCUGCCUCAGCCUCCUAAGUAGCUGGUAUUACAGGAGUGUGCCAUUAGCCUGGCUAAUUUUUGUAUUUUUAGUAGAGAUGGAUUUUCAUUGUGUUGGCCAUGCUGGUCUUGAACUCCUGACCUCAAGUGAUCCUCCUGCCUUGGCCUCCCAAAGUACUGUGAUUACUAUCAUGAGCCACCACACCUGGCCUAAAAGAUCAUUGAUUUAGUUUUGAGUAAGAUUUUAAGUGAUUAAAUUAUGGUAUUGUUGUGUCUGGAAUAUCUGAUAUUAGGGUUUUUUUUUUUUUUUUUUACAGUUUUUGAUAUGCUUUAUUUUGGGUAUGUAGUUUACAAAAUAUAAAGGAAAUAUAAGGAGUGUUCUCUUUUUUUUUUAAAUAAAAAGUGUAUUUUUAACUGGGCAUGGUGGCUCACUCCUGUAACCCCAGCACUGUGGGAGGCUGAGGCUGGUGAAUCGCCUGAGUCCAGGAGUUUGAGACCAGCCUGGGCAACAAGGUGAAACCCUGUUUCUAUCAAAAAAAAAAAAAAAAAAAAAAAAGGAAAAAAAAUAAGUCAGGCAUGGUGGUAUGCACCUGUAGUCCCAGCUACUUGAAGGCUGAGGCAGGAGGAUCGCUUGUGCCUGGGAGGUUGAAGCUACAGUGAGCUAUGGUCAAGCUACUGCACUCCAUUAUAGGCAACCCUAUCUCAAAAAAGCAAAGCAAAACAAAACAUUUUUCCCCUUGAUUAUAGAGGUUUGAGAAAAAUUUGAGGGAAGAUUCAGAAAAUUACCUGUAACUGAACAGAAUGCCACCAGCUUGGGCUUAUUCUGCAUGCAUAAUUAUGAACAUUUUCCCAGCUCUUGUGAAAAUUCUCACAUUCAUAGAAAGAUAGAUGCACCAGUAAAAUAAAUACCUGUAAAUACGAUAAUAAUUUCAUAAUAAUAUGCUUCACCUAGAUUUACCAGUUACUAAUAUUUUGCCAGUUUUAUUUUCUCACACACUUUUGUUGAGCAUCUGAAAACCAUACACAUGAUGACAGUUCAACCCAUAAUGUUUUAGUUUGCAUCUCCCAAGAAUAAGGUUUUUCUUCUGUAUAACAAGAAUAUUGUAAUCAUACCUAAGAAAAUGAAUUUUAUUACAUAUGUGUUCUAUAUUCAAAUUUCUGUAAUUACCCCUAAGAUGUCUUUUAAAUGAUUUUUAGCAUUGAUAGUCUGUGCCUGUGUAGAUUAUAACAUUGGCUAUUGCAAAAUAAUGGUUUUCUUUUUCUCUUUUUUUUUGAGACGAAAUCUUGCUCUAUUGUCCAAGCUGGAGGGCAGUGGCACAAUCUCGGCUCACUGCAACCUCCGCCUCCCAGGUUCAAGCAGUUCUCAUGCUUCACCCUCCUGAGUAGCUGGGAUUACAGGCAGGUGCCACUGUGCUCUGCUAAUUUUUAUAUUUUUAGUAGAGACGGAGUUUCAUCGAGCUGGCCAGACUGGUCUUGAACUCCUGACCUCAAGUGAUCCACCUGCCUCGUCCUCCCAAAGUGCUGGGGUUACAGGUGUGAGCCACUGCACCCAGCCUAAAAUGAUGGUUUUCUGAUUCUAGCAUUUCUUUUAUAAGAUUGCUAUGUAAAGCACAGCUUUUCUUUUUUUAGGGAAAAAUGUCUUUUAACAGCUGCAAAAUAAAUAUUCUUUCAAUGGAAUGACAAUUAUUAUUUUUGCCAUAUAUUUAUUUUAAAAAUUUAUGUAUAAUGGUAACCUGAGCCUGCAUGUUAUUCAUGUGUGGUGCCAUACUGAUCUUUAAUUUUAAUGUGAAGCAAGUACUAAUAUAGUAAAGCAUAAAUUAUAUAAAAUUUGCUUUAUAUUUUGGAUUGCAAAUUAAUUGCUGUACUUUAUAGAAAAGUUUCCCAAAUCCGUUUUACUUUUUUGUAUUUGAAAUUUAAUCACAGGUGGAAUCUUAAAGAGAGCAUUUAGGGAUAUUGUAAACAGAUGUUAUUAAGGACUAAUGUUAACAAACAUUGAAGAAGAGAAAACAGUAUUUGUUUUUAGCUUAACAUCUUAGUGGAGUGAAAUAUUUUCAGUAUAUUUAUUUUAUUUAUUUAUUAAUUAUUUUUUUUUUUGAGAUGGAGUCUGGCUGUAUUGUCCAGGCUGGAGUGCAGCGGUGCAAUCUCAGCUCACUGCAACCUCUGCCUCCUGGGUUCAAGCGAUUCUUGUGUCUCAGCCUCCCGAGUAGUUGGGAUUUACAAGUCAAUUUUUUUUUUAACUAAAACUACAGAAUCUAUUUUUCUUGGUCUCAUACUCAGUUUUUUAUGUAGUCACUUAGUAAAUAACCUAAUUUGCUUGUUUUCUCCACACUAAUUUUAGGGUGAAUUCCUCAUUUCGCUUUUCAGAUCAUGGGGUGAGGGGGAUGGUUGUGUGUGUGAGGAACUGAGGAAUCAGAUGGAAAACAAUGCCUCUGCUCCUUUGAGUAUAAUCAGUGAUAUUUGAGGUUCCAGGGUUAAAUGCUGCAUUUUUAUUUCUGACGUUCGUACCUUAAAAUAUUUGAAGAAAAUAAACUAUUUCAUUGUUGUCAGAAA